GCAGUGACAAUUUAUUUUCCUGCAGCAGCGGCAGCAGGGACGGUUGCUGCAGGUUCGGGGUCGGCCGGCCUGCGCGUGGGCUUGCGAGGACGCUGUUCGUCCCCUGCGCUGGGGUGUCCGACAGCGAGGAGGAGAACGACGCACGGAGCCCGCGCGACUGGAACCAGCAAAGCUCCAUCUGUCGGCAGAGGAGAAGGGGGAGGAGGCACGGCCGAGGCAAACGAGCGGACGCCUCGUCGCCGGGUGCCGGUAUCACCCCGCUGCAACGCCUUCCAGCAAAAGCCACCGCGGCCCGGGUUGCAGCAGCCGGACGGAUGCCAAGGCCACACGGCAGCCACGGGGGCAGCCGUCGCAGUCGCCGUCCCACACGGGCUGCGGACACCAAGGGUUGCUAGUGAGUAGCGGCGCGCGCGCGUGAGUGAGAGCGCGCACCGGACGGGGAAGUGCGCACGGCGGGUGCGUCUGCCUCGUGGCCUGGCGCGCGCCGGCCCUUCCGCUGGCAGCGUCCGGUCCCGGGCUGGCUCUAGGGGAGGAAAAAAUGCACUUUGGCGGCUGAUCGCUUCCUUCCUGCCAGUCAUGCAAUCGGCCGCCUCCAUCGGCGCCGCCUGUAUGCGCCCCUCCGCUGGGCCCUCUGGGUUAGUUUCACCUUGAUAGGGAGGCAGGAAGACCUGGCUGCUGGUGGCAGGGCGGGACUCUGGCCGUGACCUAUACGUGGGUGCGCCUGUUUUUUUGGUUCAGCCCUGGGUUGCAGCCUUGGAGAUGAUGUCGACCUUGGGAGAGACCACUGCACUGUCUCUAGCGGCGCGGUGUGGAGGAGGGAGGGGCGAGGGUUAGAAAAACGGACCUUUACCCCGGCCGAGCAGGUGCCAUGCCUUUCCAGAUGAUGUUACUUUUAUGCCCUUUAUGAGCGACUAAGACAUUGCCCCUCACCUGAAUAACUUAAAGCUUUCGCUGAAAGCCCCCAGUGAGAUGCACAAAGAAAUGGAAUGUCUCCAAAACAUAUUUUUUUCAGAACUUUCUCUAAAACAACCCACGCUGCUGAUACCCCCAGAGCCUAAGGUGCCAUAAUUGCUGAAGUUUAAAAGAAAAUUUAUGUAAGGAAUAAGUAAUUCAGGAAACGGAACCCAAUCUAGAGGUUUGAAAAAAAAAAUCAAGUGCCUGGGAAGUGGGGUGGGGUGGCUUGCUUCCUGGAAAUCAGUGUUCGGUAGUAAGUAAAAAAGACAGCUUUCAAAGUAAGCCCCAGUGAGCACACUGCUUUCCAAACAUCUUGCUCAUUACUGACAAUAACAUGAAGUCCUGGAUUUUAAGCUAUUUCCGAAGACAUAAUAGAUAUCACUAGGAUGCUUGUUUAUGGUCUCAUGAUUUAAGGCCCUGUCAAGGUCAAUAACGUAGAUUUGUUCCAGCAGAUAAAUUAUACCUGAAUGUUUGAUUGUUCGUGUCAAUUUUUUUGAGGGUAGGUUUUGACGGUUGUUUUACACAGAAAUUAAGCCACCGUGUUUUGUUUUUAUCCCGACCUUGUUUCCAUUGGAAAUUUUGUGUUUUCAGGAUGGAUGCUACAUUGCACUUCAAAAAUAUACUCUGCCACUGGAUUGUAGUGGGCAUUGUGUAGCUACACUAUACAUAUCUUUAUUUUUAAUACAAGUUAAUGUGUCGCUGAGCAGUAGGCUCUUUUUGUUUACCAUUUGCACCAUGAGAGCUUCUCCAUUCAAAGGCAUAAAAUGUUAUUGGAAUCUACCUGCAAAAUGAAUUGGCUGAUUGUUUUCUGUUCAGACACAGAUACAGCAAAUUGCCACUAAGAAUCUGCUUUUGCGUAUACGUUGGCUGUAAUUUAUGUAGCAACUGGUUCUUGGGAAUUUCAAGAAGAAACUUGUUUUCUUAUCCUCACCUAUAAAGACCCUUCCCAGCUGUAAGAAUUUACAGCUACAAUCCAAGAAAUGAGAUUGCAUUUUACAAGAAAAGAAAACUGAUGAUUCUUGCCCAAAACAUGAGAAGUAGAAGGAAUGUGAGAGAAAAUAAUGUAGAUUCCGUCCAGGAAGUGCUAGGUGCUUUCCUGGCCCAAGGAUGUGACCUUCUCUUGGAUUUUCCUGAUUAUUAUGAGAGGCAAGUCGUUAGUGUUGCAGUGUGACUGUGAGUAUAAGCCCUGAACUCCUGUGCACUUAGAGUCCCUGCUCUGUCAUUUGCUUGAAUUACUUAUCUCUUCUAGGCUUUAGUUUUCUUAUCUGUAAAAUGGAAAUCAUGGUCGUAAUCAUUUGAGUGUUUCCUGGCACCAAGCAUUGUGCUAUAUGUUUUACAAGCAUUAUCUCACUUUACCUUCUCAGUACCCCUAUUCAUUAUCAACCUCCUUUGCAGUUUGGGAAGCUGCAGUUCUGCUGUUAGUGGUUCCUGGAGCCAGAAUUUGAAUUCAGAUGUUCUAACCCUGGAGACUGCAUGUCUAAUCCCAAGGCUCAACUACCUCCUAUUGGAGAAGGCUAACUGAGAUCAUGUGUGUUCAUGCAUCCAGUUAGCCAGGGAACGAAAGCAUUCUGCUAAUGAUGAAGUGAUUGAGAAGAAACAGUGAACAUCCUCAUUUCACAGAUAAGACAACAUGGAUCAGCCUUUUACUGUGAAUUCUCUGAAAAAGUUAGCUGCUAUGCCUGACCAUACAGAUGUUUCCCUAAGCCCAGAAGAGCGAGUCCGUGCCCUAAGCAAGCUUGGUUGUAAUAUCACCAUCAGUGAAGACAUCACUCCACGACGUUACUUUAGGUCUGGAGUAGAGAUGGAGAGGAUGGCGUCUGUGUAUUUGGAAGAAGGAAAUUUGGAAAAUGCCUUUGUUCUUUAUAAUAAAUUUAUAACCUUAUUUGUAGAAAAGCUUCCUAACCAUCGAGAUUACCAGCAAUGUGCAGUACCUGAAAAGCAGGAUAUUAUGAAGAAACUGAAGGAGAUUGCAUUCCCAAGGACAGAUGAAUUGAAAAACGACCUUUUAAAGAAAUAUAACGUAGAAUACCAAGAAUAUUUGCAAAGCAAAAACAAAUAUAAAGCUGAAAUUCUCAAAAAAUUGGAGCAUCAGAGAUUGAUAGAGGCAGAAAGGAAGCGGAUUGCUCAGAUGCGCCAGCAGCAGCUAGAAUCGGAGCAGUUUCUGUUUUUCGAAGAUCAACUCAAGAAGCAAGAGUUAGCCCGAGGUCAAAUGCGAAGUCAGCAAACCUCAGGGCUGUCAGAGCAGAUUGAUGGGAGCGCUUUGUCCUGCUUUUCCACACACCAGAACAAUUCCUUGCUGAAUGUAUUUGCAGAUCAACCUAAUAAAAGUGAUGCAACCAAUUAUGCUAGCCACUCUCCUCCUGUAAACAGGGCCUUAACGCCAGCUGCUACUCUAAGUGCUGUUCAGAAUUUAGUGGUUGAAGGACUGCGAUGUGUAGUUUUGCCAGAAGAUCUUUGCCACAAAUUUCUGCAACUGGCAGAAUCUAAUACAGUGAGAGGAAUAGAAACCUGUGGAAUACUCUGUGGAAAACUGACACAUAAUGAAUUUACUAUUACCCAUGUAAUUGUGCCAAAGCAGUCUGCGGGACCAGACUAUUGUGACAUGGAGAAUGUAGAGGAAUUAUUCAAUGUUCAGGAUCAACAUGAUCUCCUCACUCUAGGAUGGAUCCAUACACAUCCCACUCAAACUGCAUUUUUAUCCAGCGUUGAUCUUCACACUCACUGUUCCUAUCAACUCAUGUUGCCAGAGGCCAUUGCCAUUGUUUGCUCACCAAAGCAUAAAGACACUGGCAUCUUCAGGCUCACCAAUGCUGGCAUGCUUGAGGUUUCUGCUUGUAAAAAAAAGGGCUUUCAUCCACACACCAAGGAGCCCAGGCUGUUCAGUAUAUGCAAACAUGUGUUGGUAAAAGACAUAAAAAUAAUUGUGUUGGAUCUGAGGUGAUAUGUUCUGAAUGUAAGCACCGUCAACAUCAGACACCUACUCAUGGACAUGUGGUUGCCGGAUUUUCUUAAGAUGUUUCCAGAAAUGACUGAUAUUUUAUAUUUAUACAUUUUAGAUGACAAAGCUUGAUAUUUAUUGCUGUUGCACAUUUUAAAGUUUUCUUUUUGGGUUGCUCUGUGUCAAGAGAGGUUACAUGGUGUUAAAUCGGUACCUGAUAAUGUACCCAAAUACUAUGGCCAGAUAAUAAAUUGUGCUGCAAACAA